UUUAUGUUUAUCAGUAAUGUUCAUAGCUUUGUUAGAAGACAAAGGCUUUAGAGCAUUCAUGUUUUGAUUUUUUUUCCUUUUGAACAUUUUUUUAAAAACUGAAGCAUAAAAAUUUUAGAUCUCUGUGAAACAAUGCUACAAUCAACUCUAUAUUUCUACCUAGAAAGGUAGGAAAAGACCACAAUUAUUUUUAGAUUUAAAGAUACUUUCUGCGUCAUAACCACUAUUUUCUUUCCUAUGCCCCCUCAUCGCACCCCCUGCCUCUCAUGAUCAUCCAGAGGCAUUUGAAGUUCAUUAAUUUCCUCCUUUUCUCUUCUAUUUGACCUCUGCAUUUAUCUAUCUUCUUGUCAAUCAUUUAUUCUGUGUGCCAGGUGCUAGGCAAGUGGCAGAGAUACAAAGAUAAAAAUCAUAUUCCUGUUCUCAAUGUACUUAAAGUCUAAAGGAGAAGACAGAUGUGCAAACAAUUGCAGUAACCACUGUAAAGGUAAAGGACAUCAGCUCAGUCUUAGUGGUUGAGCUGGGCCUGUUAAGGAAGCCAAAGGUAAUAGGUAUGACUCAAGUGUGGGCAUAUGUUAGGAGAAAGGGUAGAAGCUGAAAAUGGAAAUGCAUGCAGGCCAGCUCACAUAUGCCAUAGUGUAUGACACAAUCAGGAAUUCAAAUUUUAUCGUGAAUCAUAUUAACAAGGCAUAAAAAUUAAAGAACUGUCAGCAAGAGAAUGAAAUGAACAUAUAUGCAUUUUGAAAAGAUCUCAGCCGGGCGCGGUGGCUCACGCCUGUAAUCCCAGCACUUUGGGAGGCCGAGGCGGGUGGAUCACGAGGUCAGGAGUUUGAGACCAUCCUGGCCAACAUGGUGAAGCCCCGUCUCUACUAAAAAUACAAAAAAAUUAGCCGGGCGUGGUGGCGGGUGCCUGUAGUCCCAGCUACUCUGGAGGCUGAGGCAGGAGAAUGGCGUGAACCCGGGAGGCGGAGCUUGCAGUGAGCCGAGAUCGCUCCACUGCGCUCCAGCCUGGGGGACAGAGCGAGACCCCGUCUCAAAAAAAAAAAAAAAAGAAAGAAAAGAAACAAACAAACAAAAGAUCUCACUGGCAGCAGUGUGGAGGCAGAAUGGACAAGAUUCACAUAUUCACAUAAAAGAUGGCAGGCAGAGGUCUCAAGCACUUGCGGUAAGAAUGUGGAAGCGACACACGUGAAAGAGGUUGACUGAGGCAGGUUCUCCAGACUUUAUAGAUUGAUCUUAUGUGAGGAGUAAGUGAGAUGGAGAUAAGUCUCGUGUUUCUGGCUAGAGUGACCAGGAGUAAGAUGGUGGCAUUAAUCAGGAUUAGAGAUUGAUUCAUUUUUUAAAAUAUGUUGUAUUGGUAGUGCCACUGAGACAUCUGAAUAGAGUAGUAGAAAACCCAAUUAGAUGUGAGUUUAAGGCUCAGGAGAGAAGUAUGGGCUAUGAUAAUAUAUCGAUUUAAGAGUCAUCAUAGUUGAAGCUCUAUGAGUGACAUCAUCAGUAGUUUCAUUAAAAAUGAAAACAAACAAGGGUUAAGGGUGGCACUUAAGGGAAGGCCUUCUUAAGGACCAAACUGGGGGACUUCUAGGCCAUAUGGUGCCUUUAUGUGAAUUAGAAAGCACCUUUAUUGCUAUCGGCCAGAAAGUCAUUAUAAUGAAUUUAUGAAGAUUACAGUGUGAAUGGUACUCCCUGGUGCUGGGCAGUACACAGCCUCCCCAAACCAUGCCAUGAGGCCAGCAGUGAAAAAUCAGCUGGCAAGGAGACUAAGAAGGAGCCACCAGGCAGAUAAGAAGAAAUCAAGUGGUGUAGAAACGAAGAGAAUAGAGUUUCAAAGCCGAAAGAGUGGCACGGCUGUCAACUAUGACUCAGAAGUAAGGUACAUGGGAUCUGAAAGUAUUCGACAAUCAGUCUUCUUCUAAAUUUGGGAUGCUCUCUCUCUCCUACCUCUUGAAGGUGCUUGACCCCAGCCACUGUCUGUUGGGGUUCAAUCAGGCUGGUGGGAAAAAUAUUAGAGAUAGUUAUAGAAAUAGACACAAAUCUUGUUGGAAGGCUGAGAAGUUUGCAUAACUUUGGUAAUAGAUCUGGCUGGAGGCAGCCUGAUCCCUUUACCUUUAGUUAAACAAAUUAAAAUAGCAAUAAAGGAAGAGUAGUUUACCUAGCUAACUUGUUUACUCAUAUAAUCUUAAGACUAACCUUUGAUGUACCGUGGGUGCUUAAGUGCGUUUUACUCAGGAAGCCCACAAUGUCAAUUACCCUCUAAUGGUGUUGACUCAAGCUUUUGUUAAUUAAUCUUACUGAAUAAAUGUGAGUCUGACUAGCUGAUCAGGGCCAGUCGCAACUGUUUACAGGACUCAGCAGGGAGUCUAUAAGCGGCUCGAACACAGCUGGACUGGCAGAGGAGAAUAUCUGUGUGUCAGUGUACUUUAUUCAUCCGUCACCAGGUCAGGGGUCUGCAAGGGACAGACUCCCUGCAGCUGGUGCCCCCUUGAGAGGAGUGCUGCCGCAACUAUCCCUUCCACCCUGUCUAGCAUUUGGAUGCCCUAUACAUCAUCUUCCUUUCCGUCUUCCUUUUGCUUGAAGGUUUCCUCUCUCUCCUCCUGUUUUGAAUCUGGAUACAUUUUGGUUUGUUUCUCAUUCCUCUUACUGUUUCACAGAUGCUGCCAUUAUUUGCACCUGAGCCUGCCCUCUUAGAAUUACAGUCUUUUCUUUAGGUCUUCACAAGACAUGUUUGUUUUAAACACAAUUCUUAUAGACAUCUACUGCCCUUUACAUACGUGUGAGCAUAUAUUUGUAUUUGAAUACAGAUACCUUCUGAACAAGAUAUGAAAGGGAGUUUGAGGUCUCCUUCAUAUACGCUGUCAUCAUUUUGGACAAGGAAAAUGUUACCAGCCUGAUUUCAGACAGUUAUACCAAACCAUCUGGCCCCUUAACUCAAGUGCCUUCUUCCUCUAUAUGUAGACUUGAGUCCGGGGCAUAAAUGGAGGUCAAGUAAUAGACUCAUCAAGGGAAGAACUUUACUUCCUAUUGUGUAUUACAGUGAAACUUAUAAGAUGAAUUCACCAUAAUGUGUAUAAUGGCAUUAUUCAUGUUUUGAAUUGUGACUGAUGACUUUGCUAUACCUGGGUCAAACCUGAGCCCAUUAUUUCACUAGAACUGCACUGUUUAGUAUAAUAGCCAUUAGCCACAUGUCACUAUAUAAAAUUGAAAUGUAAUUAAUUAAAAUUAAAUAAAAAUAAAAACUCAAUUUUCCAGUCACACUAGCCACCUUUUAAGUGCUAAGUCGUUUGGCUAGUGGUUACUGUAUUGGACAGUGCAGAUUUCCACCACUACAGAAAGUUUUAUUGGACAGCACUGCACCAGAAGACUGUUGAUUGUUUCUGUUAGUUCUCGGCUUUGGAUGAUGACUCUCAGGAAAUAAGUGAGUUCCUCUGCAAUAGUGCACAAUUUAUAUUAUACCACAUAGAGGAUUUUUUUGUGUAUUUGAUAUAAUUUUUAAAAAGAGGUAAUUAACUUUCAGUCAGCAUCUUCAGUGCUCUAAGUGCUUUAUAUUAGUUAUACUUAUUGCUAAUUUAUUAUUAUUAUUAUUUUCUAUUAAUUAUCUUAUGUUGUCACCAUCAUUUUACAAAGCAGGAAAAUAGGGUUAGGAGAGGACAAGUGACACAAACUCACAUCUAUCUGGUCCAAAAUCUACCUGUUCAAAGCUGCUUUCCAAAAAUCACCACAUGGUUAUAUUUUCUUUUUUGCAAGUAAAAUAUAGUACAUGAUCAUUGGGGUAUACCCAGAAGAUAAUGGCAGAAACUUCUAGACUCCUCAAAAAGCUGUUUGUAUUCUCAAAUGGACAUUUAUUUAACAGAUCAACAUGGUGGCAGUCAUCACUACCAACUUUUAAGAACGUACUGAUAGAGUCAUUUAUUUCCUUGCUAUUAAAAAACAAGUCUGACAGGCACUAGCAGUAAGAUCUAGUUUGCAUAUUUGUCCCUUCCAAAUCUCAUGGUAAAAUGUAAUCCCCAGUGUUGGAGGUCGGGCCUGGUAAGAGGUGUUUGGGUCAUGGGGGCGGAUCCCUCAUAAAUGGCUUGAUGCCAUCCUUGCAGUAAUGAGAGGAGUUCUUGUUUUUAGUUCACACCAAAGCUGGUUGUUUAAAGAAGCCUGGAACCUCCUUCCCUCUCUUUUGCUCCCUCUCUCUCCAUGUGAGACACUGGCUCUCCUUCACCUUCCACCAUGCUUGUAAACUUCCUGAGGCUUCCUCAGAAGCAGAUGCUGGCACUAUGCUUCCUGUUUGGCCUGCAAAACCGUGAGCCAAAUAAACCUCUUUUCUUUGUAAAUUACCCAGUCUCGGGUAUCACUUUAUAGCAAUGCAAACUAACACACAGGACAUUCCAGUGAAACAAUGAUCCCAAAUUCAUUCUAGAAAUAUCUUCAUAGAAAAUCUGAGAAUCAUAAAAGAAAUUAGUCUCAGUAAUCUUUUUCUAGAAGAUGGAUGCUAUUUUGGUCAACUUAUACAUAAGACCCUGAGAAUUUAUGGAAACGACAUUAGAAGUGGUUUUAUAGUUUACCUUAAAGAUGACUUCUAAAGAAAGAACUGAUAUUUUGUAUUUUACAGAGAAGAGGAGCACUUUAUAAAAUUUCAUUUUGUUAAAUUUUUAUCUUAAAGUUGUGGUCUUUGGUUUAUGUGACAUUCUAACAAGCCAGGACUCUCUUCCUUAAGCCACACACAUGAAAAUUAAAAUAAAGUAAUUCUCCUACCACAGUGUAACUGCUUUGCAUUUAUCGUUUUUGCAGGAAAGCGAUUUAUGCUGCACACCUACCCUCCUUUGCAAAGAAGUAUUACCUAGUUGAGAGGUAAUAAUUCUUGGUUUUUGGUACACAUGAUAGAAUCAUCCAAGAUGAGUUCCUGGUGUGAAAUGUAAUUAGUGGGAAUGGUCUACAUACUUAUACUUGGGCCCAAGAAAAUCUCUAAGUCACAGCAAUUGUAUUAGGCCUGUAUGGUCAUCCACCUCUGAGGUGACUGAAUCCAUUUCAUUCCCCACAAUAUUGUUUUACCUGAAUGAAAAACUAUAUUUUGGUGUAGGAGUGAAGGAUACAAUUGGGCAUGGUGUGUGAGAACCACCAGAAGCUCAUAAAUGGUAGAAGAUUCUCAGGUAGAUGAAAAUUAUGUCGGCCGGGGGCGGUGGCUCACGCCUGUAAUCCCAGCACUUUGGGAGACAGAGGAGGGUGGAUCACGAGGUCAGGAGAUCGAGACCAUCCUGGCUAACACAGUGAAACCCCGUCUCUACUAAAAAUACAAAAAAAUUAGCCGGGCGUGGUGGCGGGCGCCUGUAGUCCCAGCUACUCGGGAGGCUGAGGCAGGAGAAUGGCGUGAACCUGGGAGGCGGAGCUUGCAGUGAGCCGAGAUUGCGCCACCACACUCCAGCCUGGGAGAGAGAGUGAGAUUCCAUCUCAAAAAAAAAAAAAAAAAAAAAAAAGAAAAUUAUGUCAGAGGUAAAGUGUAGCCUUUCAGUAGAAUCCAAAGUGGUAAAACCCAGCAUGAUUUUGUAAUCAAUAACUUGGCAAGUAGCACAGUCAACUUGCAGCAACUUUUUUCUGCUAUUUGAGUAUAGCAGCAAGUGGGAAAGAUGUCUGCGUACAAAAUGGAAAUAAAUUUGUUCUCCAGACAGAUGCAGAUUUUUUCACAUUUUUUUUUCAAGUACCUCCUCUAAACCAGGACUAUGUUGGCCCUGAAGAGACAGUGAAGACACGGCCCCUGUCUUCACAGGGAUGAUAUUCUAAUGGGGUGAUAUCAAGAGGUACAUAUAAAAUGAAACAAUGCCAAAUUGCCAUAGGGAAGAUAAUUAACAUGAAUCUGACAGAUAGUAACAUGAGGACUCAUUUACUCUACAUAGGGUGUUUAAGAGGGCCUCUAUGGGGAUGAGGCAUUUAAAGCUUAGACUUUAAGUGUAAAGCAGAAACUAUCUUUGUAAGGUGUGGUCUCCACAGAAGGCCUGUGCAAAGGCCCUGGGGUGAGAUUGGGCUCCAUCUUAGUCCAAUCUUGCACUGCUAUAAAGAAAUACGAGAGACUGGGUAAUUUACACAGGAAAUAGGUUUGAUUGGCUCACGGUUCUGCAGGAUGUGCAGGAAGCAUAUUGGCUUCUGCUUCUAGAAAGGCCUUAGGUAACAAUCAUGGCGGAAGGGGAAGAGGAAGCAGGCACAUCUUACAUGGCCAGAGCAGGAGGAAAUGGGUGGAAGCGGGGAGGUGCUACACACUUUUAAACAACCGGAUCUCAGAAUAACUCACUCAUUCACUAUCACGGGAACAGCACCAAGGAGAUGGUGCUAACCCAUUCAUGAGAACUUCACUCCCAUGAUCCCAUCACCUCCCACCAGGCCCCACCUCCAACAAUGGAGAUUAUAAUUCAACAUGAGAUUUGGUGGAGACACAGAUCCAAACCAUAUCAAGCUCUAUACCUGCUCAGCUGCCAUGUGCUCUUACAAGAUCUUUUUCUUGAUGGAAUCUUAGUGAUGGUCCAUUUAUGAUAUCAAAAUAAUUACAAAACUUUUUACAUUGUUGCUUUCAUGGAGAAAUUUGAGGUUCUCCAUUGACUUAUACAGUGGAACCCACCAUAUGCAAAUCACCCUUGUUGCUGUGACUGGGUAUGUUACUACAAGUUUAUGCAUUUUACUGUGUCCAGGAAAUAGUACUUGUUUGUCGCUUACCAGAUCUGAAUUAUUACAGAGAUUUUCAGAGGUAUGGAUAGAGGUCUGUCAAACAGGGAUAAAGCAUUAUUUUAUCUAGUCUCAGCAAAGAACAUGUCUGAUAAUUUCCAGUGUUCUUGAUGUGUUAUACCAAAAUUUGUUCUCUUACCCUACGUGUUCUGCUGAUCUGAAGCACAAAAUUUCCACAUCAUAGUGUUUGUUGAAUGGUUAAAAGAGAAGAAAAAAAUGAAUGACAUGUGGAUACUAAAAUCUAUUCCACACUUUAAGCUCCUGCUGUUUUGGUAGGUAUGUGGUGAUAGUGCAGCCAAAUGCUACCAGAGGCUACAGAACAGGUUCUGAAGACAAGGAGGCCAAUGAAAUGGAAAAAAAGCUUCAUGGUCCUUUAAAUCUGGAUGAAAUAAUAGUACUACCCAAACUCAAAGGUUCUCACAUAGAGGGAAAACAAGAAGCAUCCUUGAUGUCUGAAAGGGUCUCAGUGAUUCAGAAAUCUCCAUUUCUAGGAAAUAGCAACUAUGUCACACAGCUGAAUGUUAAAGGAGGCUGCAGAUGUUUAAUAUUAAAGAGGUCCGGAACUUAUUCUUGUUUUUGCUUUUUUUUUUUAAUUAGCUGUAUUUUAUUUUUCUGGAUUGUGGGGAUUAGAUGCUCAUUAUGAAAAGCUGAUUUUUAAAAAAACCAAUCCCUCUACUUUGACUAGAGGCUAGGAAUUAUGUCUUAAUGGUAGCUAUCUCCCAGGAGUAGAAGCAUAAUAAAGAUGCAAUUUAUUAAAUAGUGUUUCCCUUUCAUUUACUCUCAGAUACUCACUAGUCAUUGCUGGGAAGCAUAUUCAGCCAGUGAGAAUGGUUCUAUACCACUUAUUUGUCUGACUUGUUUCCCAAGGGAAUGGAUGAGGACCACCCAAAGAUCCAGCAGUCCUCACCCUUGUGCAGAAUUGAACCAAGCAGCUUGUCUUUCAUCAGGUUUUGCAUAUUGGAUCACAGUGACUUCUAUUGCCUAUUGAACUUUUUCAGAUUGUUGCAACAUUCCUUCGAGAUUUGGUACCAGGAGCAAUUAAGCCAGUAUAUUCCAAAGGUGACGCCAGAGUUUACCUGAUACAAAUACUUGGCUCAUCUGUGCUAAGACUGAUUGAGAAAAUGUACUGAAAUGUUCCAGAUGCUGGCAUAUAUUUAACCUGGCACAAGGCCUCAGACCCUGAGAGCCCUGCCCCAUGGUACCACAGGGCACACAACUUUCCCACAAAGUUCAUCUGUGGCUGUCAUGGAUAAAAUAAUGGUUUGGCUUUGCUUUAGUGCCUCUGGCCCCUUUCAGGCAAUCAAAAAUAUUUAUUGACCCCUAACUAAAUGGAAGGCACAGUGGGACUCAAUUCUCACAAUUUCUGCCUCUAAUUGGGGAAUUAAGACACACAGACAUUUAAGGAAGGGAAAGAAUAGGCUAAGUGUUAAAUAGGAAUAAAAGAAGAUGAUAAUAUGAAAUGACAUAAGGCAGUUCAUGUUUACUUGCCAAAGGACUGAUGUAACUACAGUGGGCUUGGUGGAGAGAGACACACCUGGCAUCCCAGAGUAGCGUGGGCAGGCAUCAGGGAUGAAGUCAGAUUUGGUGUGAGCAUCGGAUAGGUCAGUGAUUCUCAACCCACCCUGGACAUAAGGGCCAUCUGGAAAGAUUUCAAAAAAUGCCAAAUAGGAUGCCACCAGCCGGGCACAGAAGAGGAGUGGGAAUGUCUGAAGAAGGACAUAAAGGUUUCAGCAAACAAGCUUUGGUCUGCCAACCAAAGCUUGUUUGGUUGUAGGAGAAAGUUGGUGUGAGAGAAAAAAAGAGAGAAGGCAGAAAAGUCAGGUUGCAUCUGACUCUUAAAUGGUCUUGCAUACCAGGCCAAGGAAUUUGGAAACGUAUUUGACAAUCUUUCUUCUGUUGAGGACAAUGGAGUAAAUUUAGCCACAACGCCUGACUUUUUCAGCUGGAGAAAUAUUUGCUUUCCUCCGUAUCAUGUAUUUCCUCACUUCCCACUCUGGCCCCCUGCUUAGAAACUUCGGUUUAACAGGAAAUAAGUGUAGACACAUGCUAAUACUUCACCAGUUCCUCAUUCUCUCAAAUACAGGAUCCUGGCUGAUACUAUGGGAAUGUGAUUCAGAAAGUACAAGUACUAUGUAGAAUUCCCCUGAGUAGUAGCCAGGAGGGGUCACCAAGAGGCAGCAAAUUUAGUCUCUCCAACAAGGUAAAGCAGGCCACCCUGGGUUCUCAUCCCAUUUACAAGGACAAAGGGAGUCGGCACUAUCACCUCCAGAAUUACGGAUGCUUUCACUACAGUUUCCAUUUACUUGCUACUAUGGUUUGUUCUCGUUUCUCUGAUUUUUUUUUCUCUUUUUCCCUUUUUUGAAGAAUGGACCUGGGUAAAGUUAUGAUCAUAUUAUGGCUAAUAUUGGGCUGAAACAGACUGGAUGGAUGGAUGGAUAGAUAGACAGAUGAUACAUAGGGAUAGAUUAUUUGUGAAGAGGACUGCCUAACUAAAAGGAAAUAUUUCAGCUUACAGCUGGCACUUUAUAAGACUCUUUGCAGAUAAAAUUCUGUUAGACCUUUAAAGAAAAUAAAUUUCACACUACUGUCCUAAUGCAGGAACUUGAACACAGCACAUUAACUGUAAGUCUUUGCUUAUUCAUAUGGUGAGACUUAUUUAGGCCAGGCAUGGUGGCUCACACCUGUGGUCCCAGCAUUUUGGGAGGCCAGGACAGGAGGAUUACUUGGGUCCAGAAGCUCAAGCCCAGCCUAGUCAACAGACCGAGAUCCCCAUCCCUAUGAAAUAUGUUUUAAAAACUUAUAUAAAAUAGUAUUUCAAGUCAGUUUGUGUAUUAGUAUUAAAAGAAGUGUGUUGCUUUGCAGCUGACUAGAAGCUCAGCAUUUCCUAGCUGGGCAAGAGCUUUGAGCAUGAUUGCAGCAUCUCUGCAGAAAAACUACAUUCUAAAAGCAACGGAAAUCCUCCUGCUGCCCUUCUUCCUCUGAACUGAAGUUUAAAGACCAUGGGCACUGCUGGUGACCUCCACAGAGUGUUUCAGUUCCUACCCUCUACUCCCACUCAGCAUCACUGAACAGACACAGGCUAGACAGGGCAGUCUGCAGCCCAGACUGUGGUGAGGUGGGAACUGCAGUCCUACUACUUGGUCCAUUGAAAGAGGAGGCCAAGAGGCAGAAAAUGUUCCCUCUUAAUUUUACCGUGUAACCUUUCUUAAGGUGUGGCAUGCAACUAUGUAAUGAUCACAAUUGUUAUAUUGUUUAUACAUCAUUUAUAUUUCUAUCAUCAGAUUUUACUCAAAGGUUUACUGUGGUUGGCUUCACAAGAAGUGUAAUUCUGCGUUAUUCAGGUAUCAGGAAGUGUUUAUUAAAACUCUGGUCUUGAGCUGAGUGCCAGAGAGAAAAAAAAAAUGCCCACCUGUUGGCCAGUCUAGCUCUGGAGACAAAAUUAUAAAAUAUGAGCUAAUUAGAGAGUAAAUGAAUGCUAAAGUGAGAGAUGUUUACAACAGCUGCAGGACACAUUCUGAAAAGGAAAUCAUUGUGUGCACUGGAGUGUUUAUCUGAAACCUAGAAUUGGACUAAUGAGUAGGAUUUUAUUUCUUAGUAGUGCGGGGAAAAUGAGCAAAAUCAUGGGAGAAUGUUCCAAUGGCAAAAUGCAACCUCGGUGUGGCAAAAUAGAAGCUAAUGUGAGGAAACCAACCUGCUUUAGGUGGUUUAGUCUGAUGAAGACACACAGACUACUCAAAAGGGAGAACGAGGCAAGUCAGAAGACAGGCUCAGAGGCUAUUGCAGAAAUUCAGGCAGGAGGUAAUUCAGACCUGAACUAAUCUUAAAAAAAAAAAAAAGUACUACACAGGAAAAGCAAUAAGAAGACCCACGGGGAAUUUCACUGGAAGAGUCCAAGGGUCAUAUAAUGUUUCCAGCUAAAGAGGAAGGAACCUCUUUCAGGAGCUAUAAAAGAAAGGGAGGAAUCAUGUCCACAAUUGCAGCUUUCUAUGGCGGCAAGUCCAUUCUCAUCACGGGGGCCACAGGCUUUCUGGGCAAAGUGCUGAUGGAGAAGCUGUUUCGCACCAGCCCAGACCUGAAAGUCAUUUACAUCCUUGUGAGGCCCAAGGCUGGCCAGACACUGCAGCAGAGGGUUUUCCAGAUCCUAGACAGUAAGCUAUUUGAGAAAGUCAAAGAAGUUUGUCCAAAUGUGCAUGAGAAGAUCAGAGCUAUUUAUGCAGAUCUCAAUCAGAAUGACUUUGCCAUCAGCAAAGAGGACAUGCAGGAGCUUCUCUCCUGUACAAACAUAAUAUUUCACUGUGCAGCCACUGUACGCUUUGACGACACUCUCAGACAUGCUGUGCAACUUAACGUCACUGCCACCCGGCAGCUCUUGCUUAUGGCUAGUCAGAUGCCAAAGCUGGAAGCCUUUAUACAUAUCUCUACUGCCUAUUCAAAUUGUAACCUGAAGCACAUCGAUGAAGUUAUCUAUCCGUGCCCUGUGGAGCCAAAAAAAAUCAUUGAUUCCCUUGAGUGGUUAGACGAUGCUAUUAUUGACGAGAUUACACCCAAGCUGAUCAGAGAUUGGCCCAAUAUUUAUACCUACACCAAGGCCUUGGGAGAAAUGGUGGUGCAGCAAGAGAGCAGGAACCUGAACAUUGCCAUCAUAAGGCCCUCCAUUGUGGGAGCAACUUGGCAGGAGCCUUUCCCAGGUUGGGUUGAUAAUAUAAAUGGACCUAAUGGAAUCAUUAUUGCGACUGGGAAAGGGUUUCUUCGGGCCAUAAAAGCUACUCCAAUGGCUGUGGCAGACGUAAUUCCAGUUGAUACAGUCGUCAAUCUCAUGCUAGCUGUAGGAUGGUAUACUGCAGUUCACAGACCUAAGUCAACAUUAGUCUACCACAUUACAUCUGGUAACAUGAAUCCCUGCAAUUGGCACAAAAUGGGAGUCCAAGUCUUGGCAACCUUUGAAAAAAUCCCAUUUGAGAGACCUUUCAGGAGGCCAAAUGCUAAUUUUACCAGCAACAGCUUCACAUCACAGUACUGGAAUGCGGUCAGCCACCGGGCCCCUGCCAUUAUCUAUGACUGCUAUCUGCGGCUCACUGGAAGGAAGCCCAGGAUGACAAAGCUCAUGAAUCGGCUUUUAAGAACUGUUUCCAUGUUGGAGUAUUUCAUCAACCGGAGUUGGGAAUGGAGCACGUACAAUACAGAAAUGCUGAUGUCUGAGCUGAGUCCUGAAGACCAGAGAGUAUUCAACUUUGACGUGCGCCAGUUGAACUGGUUGGAAUACAUUGAAAAUUAUGUUUUGGGAGUUAAAAAAUACUUAUUGAAAGAGGAUAUGGCUGGGAUCCCAAAAGCAAAGCAACGCUUAAAAAGGUCCUGCACUCCAUACUCUACCCUGUAACACAGUUUCAUUUAGACUUCACCACACCUCUAUGAGGCAAGUAUUACUUUUGUUACCCCAUUUUUAUGAGGCAGAUAUCUAGAUUUAAACACAGCAAAUAACUUGCCCAUGGUAAUUGCAUAGUAAGUCUAAGAGCCAGAUUUGAACCCAAAUUUGUUUCUUCUACCACACUCUGUCAUAAUGGGAUAUAAAUACCCAACAGGCAGGAGACCUGAUUAUGCUAUUUAACCUAGAAAAAAGUCACUCCUCAAUUUUUUCAACUUUCUUAAAUUUCUUUCAGUCGUAAUCCCUGAGGGACAAGGAAUUCUAGCACUCUGGUAUAAUCCUGGUAGAAGCAGAGGAUCUGUAGUGCAGAGAUGAUAAGGAUAAAAAAGUAGCUUGCAAAACAGGAAGGAGGAACCUUGAAUAGCAAGCCAAGAACUUUAGAAUUUACCUUCUAAUGAACAAGAACCAGUGAAGAUUUAUGAUGUGGUAACAUGACCAAAGUAUAUUUACAAGAUUAUGCUAGUCAUGCUUGUAAAUAGUUUCAAGUGGAGAGAGGUAUAAGAGAAAUUAGGGAAAUAUGGUAGAAAUCUGACUAUUCAGCAAGAAUGCUGUGGAAAUGAAAGACGCAGAAACCAAUUGGCCAAGUUAUAUCAAAUACUCUGAGCACUUCAUAAAUACUUGCCAGUCAUAUCCAGGAAAACACAUAUUUAUCUUCAGAUAAUGUGGUUGGGUAUCUGGUAGUUUUAACUUUGGUUAUGUCUGUCUGUUCCCUAGGCUCCGAAAUAUUCACUACCUCUUUAAUACUGCCCUCUUCCUUAUCGCCUGGCGCCUUCUCAUUGCAAGAUCUCAGAUGGCUCGGAAUGUCUGGUUCUUCAUUGUAAGCUUCUGUUAUAAAUUCCUCUCCUACUUUAGAGCAUCCAGCACGCUCAAAGUUUAAGAGCAUUUAGCCAUCGCUUUUUAUCUGGAACCUCUCAGAUACCUCUAAAACAGCAAACUGUGAUUCUCAAGAUUAGAAAGUAACAAGGAAUAUGCCCAAACUGUCAAAUGUCACCUGUUAUGUAUUCGUCCCUAUUCCUUAACUAUGUAUUUUUAUUUCAGUGAGAGAAGGAAAGUUGUAAACUAGCCCAUAGUCACCUAUAUUUUAGGGAAAAAAAUCCAAAUUGUUUCCUAACAUUCUAUUUUAUGCCCUUGCGUAUUAAACGUGAAAGUACUCCCACUUUUCUAUAUUUAGUUUUUCUUUUCUCUCUGAGAUGAUUCAUUUAAACUCAGUAAAUAUGGAAAGAUGCAUGGCAGAAGCUGAAAUGAGCUCAAGCAGUACUAACCUUGGAACCAUUCUGGGUACCCAAAAGAAAAAUUUAAAAUCAAGAUGAGUAAAAGGAGAAUGGUCUCAAUAUCCUCAAAAAUGCAGUAAGAGAAGUAAUUCCCCACUGAAAAUGUCUCUCUUUCUUUCUAUGUUAUACCCUGGAGUCCUGGUUGAGGGGUGGGGGAAUCAGAAAAGUAGGUUUACAUUUAACAUUUUUCUUAACUACAUUCACUUCUUAAAAAGGAACAAGAAGUGUAAAUAAGUAUGUAUAGAGUGAGGGAUUAAGCAUAUUUGCAUUGGGGACUCGUGUAUUAUGCUUUUAAGUCAAAAUUAAUAUUCUCAAAUUCGAAUUUGAUAGCUAUUAUUUCUAAAUCUUUUUAAUCCUCAAUUUUCCUGGUAACCUUCUUUCAAGAGUCUCCUUCUUCUAAAAGUUGCCAAACCCUUUAUAUUUAAGCUUUUUCCACUCAGGACUCAAUUAGAGUGGUCAACAGGGAGAGGGAUGGUCCCAUUUGAUCUUUGCCACUGAGCAAAACAAAACUUCAAAUGAACUUUUAAACUGUAGCUUUAGUCUUCUGGUAUAAAGUGGGGAAGAUUACACUUAUGUGAUCACCAAAGGAUUUACUAGUAUCUUGGUCAUUCCAAUUGCACAAUGUUAACUGUACAACACACAGCAGAAAAGUGAAUAGACUUCACUAAGGGAUUCUAAGUUUAGAAAAUAGGUUUUGUUUUCUUAAAAAAUUUUGUGUAUAAUACAAACUAAUGAAAACUAUACAUAUUCUCCAAUUCCUAUAGUAAUAAUAAUGUAACUGUUACACCAACUUUCCUCAUAUUUGAGAGAUGAGUACAUGUUGGAUUGCAGCAUUUCUUCAUGUUAAAAACAUGGAAUAUUAUUCAAAUAUAGUACUUGGGGCCUAAACAACUAAAAUUAGUCACCGCAUAACUAGUUGAAAAUGGCAUAGGCAUAAAAUGUUAAUAAAGAAUGGCAGUUAUAUUUAUGCUCACUUCCUGGAGUAAUUGGGUAAUAUUCAGAAAGGCACAUCGUGGUAGUUUAAGUGUACAAGGCCUUAGGGCAGUAUCUAGCCCAGUAUUAUUCCAGAUUCUCCUGAGCUCUAUAUAAAGGGCAUUUUGGAGGAACUCUUCUGGGCAAUAUCUUUCCCAAUCUCAUCUAAAUUCUGGGAAAUAUUUUCCAUAGCAGACAACCCAGCUCUGAAACUAAGCACCUGGUGAUCUUUAGUUUGAGAUGUCUAUAUGGUACUUUUGAGUUAUAUCAAUUAAGAUACAAGCUAUAGACAUGAUAAAAAUAUGAAAUCAAGAUAUAGCUCAGUGGGAUUGGAUUAAGACAUAAUAAUAGUUCUAAGAAUUCACUUUUGAUUGUAUGUUUUACCAAUUCAAUAAUUCCACUAAUCAAGUAUUCACAUUUUGACUUUUGAUUAAAUAAAAAUUUGAAUUAAAAUUA